CGUUUCCAUGGCAGGUGCAUAGUAAAGCCUUUCUUUUUCUAACGACUUAAUGAUUUAAUCUUCUUAUUUUCUCAGCAGACAACGCUUUGGACUUCCCUGGAUACAUUGGGACGUUACCAGUCACAUUAAUUAAUACGAGUUUCACAACUUGGGAACCAGCGAACGUGCUUCUCCAGACUUAGCUUCUGCACGGCCGUUUCUGCUUUCCUUUAUGAAGUGCGUUUCUCUAAGAGCCUGGCAGUCUCAUGGGGCUCGUCUGUUGCUGGAAGUGAGCAGCGGGUUCCAUUGCCCCCCGCCUCGGUGGGGCUCAUUGUGCAGCUUGCUGGCAAGUGGCUGGGCUCGGAGGGGCGGUGACGGUGACACACGCCAGGGGAAAGUGAGUGACCUGCAGGAAGAAGGCAAGAAUGCCAUCAACUCACCGAUGUCCCCCGCCCUGGUGGAUGUUCACCCUGAAGACACCCAGCUUGAGGAGAACGAGGAGCGCACGAUGAUUGACCCCACUUCCAAGGAAGACCCCAAGUUCAAGGAACUGGUCAAGGUCCUCCUCGACUGGAUUAAUGACGUGCUGGUGGAGGAGAGGAUCAUUGUGAAGCAGCUGGAGGAAGACCUGUAUGACGGCCAGGUGCUGCAGAAGCUCUUGGAAAAACUGGCAGGGUGCAAGCUGAAUGUGGCUGAGGUGACACAGUCCGAAAUAGGGCAGAAACAGAAGCUGCAGACGGUGCUGGAAGCAGUACAUGACCUGCUGCGGCCCCGAGGCUGGGCGCUCCGGUGGAGCGUGGACUCAAUUCACGGGAAGAACCUGGUGGCCAUCCUCCACCUGCUGGUCUCUCUGGCCAUGCACUUCAGGGCCCCCAUCCGCCUUCCUGAGCAUGUAACGGUGCAGGUGGUGGUCGUGCGGAAACGGGAAGGCCUGCUGCAUUCCAGCCACAUCUCGGAGGAGCUGACCACAACUACAGAGAUGAUGAUGGGCCGGUUCGAGCGGGAUGCCUUCGACACGCUGUUCGACCACGCCCCGGAUAAGCUCAGCGUGGUGAAGAAGUCUCUCAUCACUUUUGUGAACAAGCACCUGAACAAGCUGAAUUUGGAGGUGACGGAACUGGAGACCCAGUUUGCAGAUGGCGUGUACCUGGUUCUGCUCAUGGGCCUUCUGGAAGACUACUUUGUUCCUCUCCACCACUUCUACCUGACUCCGGAAAGCUUCGAUCAGAAGGUCCACAAUGUGUCCUUCGCCUUUGAGCUGAUGCUGGACGGAGGCCUCAAGAAACCCAAGGCUCGUCCUGAAGACGUGGUUAACUUGGACCUCAAAUCCACCCUGAGGGUUCUUUACAACCUGUUCACCAAGUACAAGAACGUGGAGUGACGGGGGAGCUGUGGAUGGUGGCAGGAGUGUCCCAGCAAGAAAGGCGGCAUCCGUCUGUGCCCUGUGCCUUUCCAGGGAGCCAGGCGCCAUGGGCUUCUGGUCCAAGCUGUGUUGACUGUCAUCCCCACCCCACCCCUACCUCACGCCUGCCCCACCCCCUGCCUCUUUUGGUUGUUGUUCUUAAUCUCCUCUCCAUGUAGUUCCCAGUGGGCAAGAGCCUUUGAAAAUGCAGGAUUCUAAACACUCGUGCUUGCGUUUGAAGCCUCGCGUCACUCAGUCGCGUGGGAUGAUGAGUCCGUUGUUGUCUGCCUUGGCCGAAAGAUGAAAAAAAGCCUGAACCCCAACCCCCAGCUGGUUGAGAGCACCCUGCAUUCUGCCUCAUGGUGCAGUUAGCGAUCACAGGCCUUCAGAAGUACAACAUCAGCUCAGCAGGAACGCCGGCUCCCCGAGGACCCAGGCUUGACGAUUCACCGGGGAUCUCCUGGGCUGGGCUCUCCUUGGAAGUGAGGCCUUUUAUUAAAAAUAAAAGGGUUUUGCAGUUUGAAAAACUUUAAAGUCCCAGAAGCUUAGAUGUGACAUGGGUGUCCUCCACCCACAUUCCUAUCACUUCUUGGUCACUCGUUUUAAUGUAGGUUUUGCACAAACAUCCAAGACUCAGGAUGGCCCAGCUCCCACAGUCCUUGAAAGGAGCUGUCUGCUGGGGACGUUUCUUAAUUUCUUGCUGUGGUUGAGGGGCUGGGUCUGGAGAUGGCUCUAAUUGUGCUGCUUGAGACAGCUUGGGUCACAGCUUUCCCCUUCAGAGGCCCUUUUUGGGAAUGAAUGCAUCUUUGGAAACUUUAAAAUGAGGGGGGUGCAUUGGUUCACUGGCACUGUGUAGUAAAGUGCCACAGGGGAGUGGCUCAGACAUCAGAGAAUUACAUCCUCAGGCCUUUCGCCUUGGCUUGUAGAUGCCGGCUUCUCCCCGUGUCUUCACAUGGUCUCCCCUCUGUGUGUCUGUGUCCUCACCGCCUCUUUUAUUUUAUUUUUUAUUUUUGUUUUUAUUUUUUGAGACAGAGUCUCGCUCUGUCACCAGGCUGGAGUGCAGUGGUGUGAUCUCAGCUCACUGCAACCUCUGCCUCCCAGGUUCAAGCGAUUCUCCUGCCUCAGCCUCCCAAGUAGCUGGCAUUACAGGCAGGUGCCACCACACCUGGCUAAUUUUUGUAUUUUUAGUAGAGACGGGGUUUCACCAUGUUGGCCAGGAUGGUCUUGAUCUCCUGACCUCAUGAUCUGCCUGCCUCAGCCUCCCAAAGUGUUGGGAUUACAGGCGUGAGCCACUGUGCCCAGCCUAUUUUUUUUUUUUUUUUUGAGACAAGUUCUCACUGUGUCACCCAGGAGUAAAGUGGUGCCAUCUCAGCUCACUGCAGCCUUGAUCUCCCAGGCUCAAUUGAUCCUCCCACCUCAGCCUCCCAAGUAGCGGGGACCACAAGUGCACACCACUAGGCCCAUCUAAUUUUUGUAUUUUUUGUAGAGAUGGGGUUUCACCAUGUUGCCCAGGCUGUUCUCAAACCCCUGGGCUUGAGCGACCCACCCACCUCAGCCUCCCAAAGUGCUGGGAUUAUAGGCAUGAGCGGACAUGCCCAGCCUGCACCCCUCUUUUUAGAAGGGCUGCGGUCCUAUUGGAUUAGGGCCCACUUAUAUGACCUCAUUUAAUCUUGAUUACCUCCAUAAAGACCCUGUCUCCAAAUACCAUCACAUCAGAGGUGCUGGGGUUAGGACUUCAGCAUGUGGAUUUGUGGGGGGCAUAAUUUGCCUUGUACCGGGAGGAUAUGAAGUGUUCAUGUUACUCUCCCUGUAGCCCUGAGAGCAUCUCCCUUAGAGUAUCCUAUAAAAGGAGUCGCUGCUCACUCAGUUAUGGGUUGUUCACCCCCUCGCUCACCCCAGCUCUGCAGAGAACUGGGGAUCCCAUCGGCCAUGCUUUCUGGGCUGGCCUCUGGUCGCAGUCAGUCCCUCGCUGUGGCGCCCCCCCCUCCCCCAGCUCCUUCCCAGGGUGAUGACCCGCUGACCCCCUGGGGUGCACCUGCUGCAAAGCAGCCCCCUUCCUUGGCAUCUCUCAGCAUUCUCCGUAGUGAGCCUGGCCUUUCUGAUCUUGUUAGCUUUUUGUCUUCCUGCCGCAGAUCAGAGCUUUGGAGUAAGUUUUGAUAUGAAAUCGAAUGCCAACACCGAAGUUUUAGAAAACAGUUUAAUAUUCCCUCUCAGUUCCGGCUGUUGCUAGGCUGGGGAUGGGUUCAGAAUAGCCAUUUUGAUGGAGGUGAUUUCCCAGCAGGGGAAAGAAAUAAUUAAAACAGCAUUACGGUGUCUCUUGCGGGAUGCAGUGACAUUCAAAAGCCACACUGACAAAAAGCCUGGGGCUGGAACGUUCUGUGCUGCCUGCAUGGCAUGUACAGGACCGCGGCCCCCUGGAGCUGGUGGAGUGGCCCAGCCUUGCCCUGCUCACAGGUGGACCUGGAGAGGGCACUGUGCCUUCCCAGGGAUUGGGAUUUGAAAAGAACAGAGCUUGGCCAGGUGCGGUGGCUCACGCCUGUAAUCCCAGCACUUUGGGAGGCUGAGGCAGGUGGAUCACUUGGGGUCAGAAGUUCGAGACCAGCCUGGCCAACAUGGUGAAACCCCAUGUCUACUAAAAAUACAAAAAUUAGCCAUGCAUGGUAUGUAUGCCUGUAAUCCCAGCUAUUCGGGAGGCUGAGGCAGGAGAAUUGCAUGAACCCAGGAGGUGGAAGUUGCAGUGAGCUGAGAUCAUGCCACUGCACUCCAGCCUGAGCAACAGAGUGAGACUCUGUCUCAAAAAAAAAAAAGAAAGAAAAAAGAAAAAGAAAAGAACAGAGCUGUGAUUUUCAGCCAAAAUGAGCAGCCCUGGCCCAUUCUGUGUCAUCAGAGGGGAGAGGACGGUUACUGUGGGAGGGGGCUUCAGCUUCUCAGGGAGGUCCUGGCGGCCCCCAUCUAGUAAACCAGUAAACCCAUGCCUAUCCUCAUGCCCACGUCACACUCUUGUGGGUUUCAAGUCGAACAGUAAAAGGAAUCAUAAGAUCUGUGGGGAAGCUACAUGGGCACUUGUGUUUCACAACAGGGACCCUUAAAGGCGAUGUUUCCAGCAAAGGAUGUGAUUUUUUUUUUUUUUUUUUUUGAGAUAAGUUCUCACUGCGUUGCCCAGGCUGGAGUGCAGUGGUCAUUCACAGACACACACAUAGCAGACUACAGACUACAGCCUUGAACUCCUGGGCUCAAGUGAUCCACCCACUUCUGUAUCCUGAGUCCCUGGAACGGCAGGUGCACACCACCGCACCCGGCUUGGAUGUGAUCUUUUGUCCACAUUCUUUUCCAAUUGGUUCAAAGGUGUAGGUGUGCCUUUUGCAUACCUGGGAAGGGCCCCAUUAGGCUCGACUCCUCAUUUUUCUCCAUUCACCAUCAGUUUGAGUCUGAAUUCAUAGCAUGGCCUGGACAGAUGCAGCAAGGGGCCAGUUCCAAGGCAGAAUUCAGGGUGAACUCGAUUCCUAUAGGCUUGGGAUGAAUGGCUGCUGGGACAUGAGGCUUGGGUGUGAGAUGCCCCGUCUGCUGCUGCUCUUGGUUCUUAGUUCAGAGAAAUUCUGGGACCCUUCCUCCUCCCGGCACCACGUUUUCAGUGAAUGGUUCUUUGAAGAGGAACCCUGGUCCAUAGGAACUGAGUGAAAGCAAGGCCAAGUAUGUCCACCCAUGGGGACAAACGUCCCAGCACAAAGGGGUCUCAGGCCUGCAAGGCCCAAGUGGACGCUCGGACAAGGGCAGGAAGGUAUUUGCUGAUUCUCCUUCUCCAUGUGACGUGUCUCUCAACCCACACCAGCUAGGGGAGCCUCCCGCAGCUUCAGUUCCCCUUUGACGCCCACACAGUGUUAUGCAAGCACCGAGCCCAGAGUCCCGCUGGGCCGUGGUGUCCUAAUUGUCUUGGUGACAAAGAGCAAUUUUAUUUUAAAGCAACUGAAUCCUUUCCCCCUGUUUUGUGUGCCAGUAUUUUACUGUCUUCUUAAUUGUUUUAAGCAAUGUUUACUUUGGAUUUCUGGAUGUUAUAUAAAAGCCACGAAAACCCUGGCCAUGCUGUUUGUCAGGCCCACCUGGCUGAGUGCAGGAAGCAAGCGCUUUUCAGGAGCUCACUGCAACACCGGGCAAACACUUCUUCCGCCAGGGAUGCGGUUAGGACAAUGCCACGUGGCGUCACAGUAUGCUGUUAUUUAUUCCAAUAAAGACCUCGUGAGCA